ACUCCCCCUCGCCCCUCGCUGGGCUUGGCCUUGGCGGCCGUGCUCUGCAGGCAGUGCCUCCCUCGGGCGUGGGUCUGCAGGAGAGCCGGACAGGGCAGCGGCCGGCACUACCGCGCUGCGAUUUGCGCAGAGCUGAAGAAGCCCCUGACCAUUGAAGAGGUGGCCCCCGCCCCGUCGGGCCUCACGAGGUCAGAGUUGAUGUCCAUUUCUGUGGAGUUAACUUUGGUGAUAUUUUGAUCUGCCGUGAUCAAUAUCAGGAAAGGCCCCAUCUUCCCUUCACACCUGGAAUGGACUUUUCUGGGACAGUAUUGGAGACAGGCACAGAUGUCAGGACAGUUAAAGAGGGAGAUAGAGUUAUUGGCACAAGAAACUUUAAUUGUAUGGCUGAAGAAUGCGUCACUGACCAGAAGGACCUGUGGCAGAUUCCAGAAAAGGUCUCCCUAUAAGAAGCUGCUGUCCUCCCUAUAACUUAUGGCACUGCGAUUUUUGCUCUUGAGCAUUGGGCCCGUACCCAGCCUGGGUAAUAUAGCUGCUGCUGGAAGUGACGAGAAGUGCAAGCUGGCGAUGCAGAGGGGUGCGCAGUCCAGCGUGAACUACAGUCAGGGCAGCCUGAAGGAUGCACCUGGCAUGGGAGGGCAGGAUUGUGGUGGUGGGAUUUGCUGGAGGAAACAUUGCUUCUGAACCAGCCAACCUUCUGCUCCUGAAGAAUAUCUCUGCUAUGGGCCUGUACUGUGGUCAAUACAAAGAUAUGAACUUUCCCGUCUUCUCCAAGAGCCUAUCUUCAGUGCUUCAGUACUGCCAGCAAGGGUGCAUCCAGCUAUAUGUCAGAAUGGUUUUCAAGCUGGACGAGAUAAGCAGAAGACAUCUUUAGGAUUCUUUUGUGUGUUUGGAACAGAGAGAGGAAAAACCCAGAUCCAUUUAAGAUUCAGCAGAGGGCUUGGAAGCCUAAGAGUUCAGGAAGAUAAAAUAACUGCACAACUUACUCAAAACCCAGGACAAAUUCAGAGAGUCAAGGAUGGAACUUUGGGCUCCCCAGAGGCUGCCCCAGACACGAGGGAAGGCCACAGCACCCUCAAAGGAUCCAGACCGAGGGUUUCGGAGAGAUGGACAUCAUCGGCCUGUCCCUCACUCUUGGCACAAUGGAGAGAGGUUUCACCAAUGGCAAGACAACCGUGGGAGCCCCCAGCCACAGCAGGAGCCCAGGGCAGACCAUCAGCAGCAGCCCCAUUAUGCAUCCAGGCCAGGGGACUGGCAUCAGCCUGUGUCUGGAGUUGACUAUUACGAAGGUGGUUAUCGCAAUCAGUUGUAUUCAAGGCCAGGUUAUGAGAAUUCAUAUCAGAGCUAUCAGUCUCCCACAAUGAGGGAGGAAUAUGCUUAUGGAAGUUAUUACUAUCAUGGACACCCACAGUGGCUGCAGGAAGAAAGAGUGCCAAGGCAACGGAGUCCUUAUAUCUGGCACGAAGAUUACCGAGAGCAAAAGUACCUUGAUGAACAUCAUUAUGAAAACCAGCACAGUCCAUUUGGAACAAAUAGUGAGACCCACUUCCAAUCUAACAGUAGGAACCCUUGUAAAGACAGCCCUGCUUCCAACUCUGGACAGGAGUGGCCGGGGGAGCUGUUUCCAGGGAGCCUGCUUGCUGAGGCCCAGAAAAAUAAGCCAUCAUUGGCUAGUGAGUCCAACCUUCUCCAGCAGCGUGAGUCUGGUCUCAGCUCCAGCAGCUAUGAGCUCAGUCAGUACAUCAGAGAUGCCCCGGAGCGGGAUGAUCCCCCAGCUUCAGCAGCUUGGAGUCCAGUUCAGGCUGAUGUCUCCUCAGCUGGUCCCAAAGCACCCAUGAAGUUCUACAUCCCUCAUGUUCCUGUGAGUUUCGGGCCAGGAGGUCAGCUGGUGCAUGUAGGUCCCAGCUCUCCCACUGACGGGCAAGCAGCCCUUGUUGAACUGCACAGCAUGGAGGUUAUUCUUAAUGAUUCCGAAGAGCAAGAGGAGAUGAGAAGUUUCUCAGGACCCUUGAUUAGGGAAGAUGUACAUAAGGUGGAUAUUAUGACGUUUUGCCAGCAGAAAGCAGCUCAGAGCUGCAAAUCUGAGACACUGGGGAGCAGAGACUCAGCUCUACUGUGGCAGCUCUUGGUUCUCCUUUGUCGCCAGAAUGGGUCCAUGGUGGGGUCUGACAUCGCUGAGCUGCUAAUGCAAGACUGCAAGAAGCUGGAGAAGUACAAGCGGCAGCCCCCUGUGGCCAACCUCAUCAACCUGACCGAUGAGGACUGGCCAGUGCUGAGCUCUGGGACCCCGAACCUGCUCACGGGAGAGAUCCCCCCCAGUGUGGAGACACCUGCGCAGAUCGUGGAGAAAUUCACUAGGCUGCUCUACUAUGGAAGGAAGAAGGAAGCCUUGGAGUGGGCCAUGAAGAACCACUUGUGGGGCCAUGCUUUGUUCCUGUCCAGCAAGAUGGACCCACAGACCUACAGCUGGGUCAUGAGUGGCUUCACCAGCACGCUGGCGCUCAAUGACCCACUGCAGACCCUCUUCCAGCUCAUGUCGGGGAGGAUUCCACAGGCAGCCACGUGUUGUGGAGAAAAGCAGUGGGGAGACUGGAGGCCUCACUUGGCUGUGAUUCUGUCGAAUCAGGCUGGGGACCCAGAGCUGUAUCAGCGUGCGAUUGUUGCCAUUGGGGACACCCUGGCUGGGAAGGGGCUUGUGGAGGCAGCUCACUUCUGCUAUCUCAUGGCUCACGUGCCCUUUGGCCACUACACCGUGAAGACAGACCAUCUGGUCUUGCUGGGCAGCAGCCACAGUCAAGAGUUUUUGAAAUUUGCAACAACUGAGGCAAUCCAGAGGACGGAAAUCUUCGAGUACUGUCAGAUGCUGGGCCGCCCCAAAUCCUUCAUCCCUUCUUUCCAGGUGUAUAAGCUCCUUUAUGCUUCCCGUCUGGCAGAUUAUGGCCUCGUGUCCCAGGCUUUGCAUUACUGCGAAGCCAUUGGUGCAGCUGUCUUGAGCCAGGGAGAGAGCAGUCACCCUGUGCUAUUAGUGGAACUCAUCAAGCUAGCAGAGAAACUGAAGCUGUCAGAUCCUCUGGUUUUAGAAAGACGCAGUGGAGACAGGGACCUGGAGCCAGAUUGGCUAGCGCAACUUCGGAGGCAGCUGGAGCAAAAGGUAGCAGGAGACAUUGGGGAUCCUCAUCCUACUCGCUCAGAUAUUUCGGGAGCCGGAGGAACAACAACAGAAAACACUUUCUACCAGGACUUUUCUGGAUGUCAAGGCUACUCUGAAGCCCCUGGGUACCGCUCAGCUCUGUGGCUGACACCUGAGCAGACCUGCCUGCUCCAGCCCAGCCCACAGCAGCCCUUUCCCCUCCAGCCGGGCUCCUACCCAGCAGGAGGGGGUGCAGGGCAGACAGGGACACCGAGGCCUUUUUACUCAGUUCCUGAGACCCAUCUACCAGGGACUGGCAGCAGCGUGGCAGUGACAGAGGCCACUGGAGGAACAGUCUGGGAGGAAAUGCUGCAGACACACCUGGGCCCUGGAGAGAACACAGUGUCUCAAGAAACUUCCCAGCCUCCUGAUGGCCAAGAGGUCAUUUCCAAACCACAGACACCAUUGGCUGCUAGACCACGAAGUAUUUCUGAGAGUUCCGCCAGUUCAGCCAAGGAGGAUGAGAAGGAGUCCUCUGAUGAGGCUGAUAAAAACUCUCCCCGAAAUACUGCCCAGAGAGGCAAGCUCGGAGAUGGGAAGGAGCAUACAAAGAGCUCAGGGUUUGGCUGGUUCAGCUGGUUUCGAUCGAAGCCCACCAAGAACGCAUCCCCCGCUGGAGACGAGGACUCCUCAGACAGCCCUGACUCUGAGCAGGAGACCCCCAGAGCAUCUUCUCCCCACCAGGCUGGCCUGGGCCUCUCACUGACACCUUCCCCUGAGUCCCCACCUCUGCCGGAUGUUAGUGCCUUCUCCAGGGGCAGAGGUGGGGGUGAAGGCCGAGGAUCCGCAUCCAGCGGGGGAGCAGCUGCGGGCGCUGGGGUUGGAGGCUUGUCUGGACCAGAGAGUGUUUCCUUUGAGCUCUGCUCCAACCCUGGUGUUCUUCUUCCUCCACCUGCCUUAAAAGGGGCUGUUCCUCUUUACAACCCAUCUCAGGUGCCUCAGCUGCCCACGGCCACUAGCCUGAAUCGGCCAAAUCGCCUAGCUCAGCGUCGCUAUCCCACCCAGCCAUGCUGAGAAUAAACACACGUCCCAGGCUCAUCUCCCAGGACUGAAACUUUCUUGCUCUCUUUUUCUCAAUCUCCCAGCCCCUCUCUACCAUAUUGGGACCCUCAAGAGGUUUGUGCUAGCCCGAUGCCUCCACCGGGCACUUAGAAGGCAAGAGGACAGGAUCUCUCAAGACACAGCACAAUUCAGUCUCUUAAGAUUAGCUUCACAAUGAUGGAAAUUAUUUCAUCAGGUGGAAAGUCUGGGUCUAAUAGCAGACUGCACAUGAGCAGAGUGACAUGGUGGUGGCACUUAUGGUGGUGGCUUGAGAGCCUUGGGGAAAUUAGGGCCCUAACAGCUAGAAUCAAAGAUGAUACCGCAGGGCCCUGUAGCAAGAAAUGGGAAGCAGGGGGAGGGGCAGGGGCUCAGAACAAUAUUCUAGACCAACUUUGACUACUUCCUGUCUUAGUAAUAGACCAAUACAUGGCUCUAUUUAGCAAAGUUUUUAUACUGAAACUUGAUUAUUGCUGCCCUUUAUAAUUUCCUCUUCAAUGAUAUUUCAGCAGUUUCCCUCUUGGUCCUAGUUUUGUGCACAUUUUUUUGAAUGUGGUUCAGAUUAAUUAUAUUUCUCUCACUUUCUUAGCUGGUCCUAUUUUUUCACAUUCUGGCAUGUGGCUAUCAAGUUAGAUUGCUGUAGGCAUCAUAUUGUCAUGGUAACUACUGAACCUAAUGAUGCAGAUGGAUGGCACAUCAGUAUAAUAAAUGAUGGAAAACGGUUCCUAAAAAUUCAUCCCUUUCAUAAGAGGGGAAGAAUGAGUGCCUGAUAUUGUUAAUACCUCCCUUUCUACCUCAGGCCUUUGCAAAUUGAUGUUCAGAGGGUCACUGGAGUGAGAGGGAGGAGGGGGGCGUCUUGGAAAUUUCCAUUUCUCUUUUCAAACCCAAAAUAGGAAUGACUCUUGCUGUUUGUCAGAUUUGCUGAAAAUUGCUCCUCACAAAGAACAUUUUUUUUUGUACAUGUAAUUGUAAAUACAGGUUUAGUACGUUAAUGUUCUAUAGUUCUGAUAUUGAUAAUAAUUAAACCCAGAUAAUUUUAUAGCAAA